GCCUGGGGCCGGGGCUGGAGCCGAGCGCACGCCCAGAGCUCCGCGCUUCCGACUGCAGCCAGAGCCCGCCGACCCCCGCCCCACUUUAAAAACUUGGACUCGGGCGCCACGUGUUCACUUCCCCCACUGUGCUUUAGUUGAAAAGGGUUUUGUGACUUUUCCACUCGAUUGCCGCCAAGCGGGCUAUUACGCCGCUUCUGACCCCACCGUGGAGACGCGGGGACUAGAGUGACCAUGCCUUCUUCGGAGCGAGCUGUCUCCAUCAUCCGCUAACGCGCCACCUUUAAAAAACAGGCACAACGCGCAAGCGACAAAGUCAGAGGCAGAGAGCGGCGGAGCACAUGAUAGAAAAGGUCGAGAGGCACAUUCAGCGCCAGGUCUGAGCAGAGGGCGGGGUGCAGGCGGAAUGGCCCUCGUGCCCUAUGAGGAGACCACGGAAUUUGGGUUGCAGAAAUUCCACAAGCCUCUUGCAACUUUUUCCUUUGCAAACCACACGAUCCAGAUCCGGCAGGACUGGAGACACCUGGGAGUCGCAGCGGUGGUUUGGGAUGCGGCCAUCGUUCUUUCCACAUACCUGGAGAUGGGAGCUGUGGAGCUCAGGGGCCGCUCUGCCGUGGAGCUGGGUGCUGGCACGGGGCUGGUGGGCAUAGUGGCUGCCCUGCUGGGUGCUCAUGUGACUAUCACGGAUCGAAAAGUAGCAUUAGAAUUUCUUAAAUCAAACGUUCAAGCCAACUUACCUCCUCAUAUCCAAACUAAAACUGUUGUUAAGGAGCUGACUUGGGGACAAAAUUUGGGGAGUUUUUCUCCUGGAGAAUUUGACCUGAUACUUGGUGCUGAUAUCAUAUAUUUAGAAGAAACAUUCACAGAUCUUCUUCAGACACUGGAACAUCUCUGUAGCAAUCACUCUGUGAUUCUUUUAGCAUGCCGAAUUCGCUAUGAACGGGAUAACAACUUCUUAGCAAUGCUGGAGAGGCAAUUUACUGUGAGAAAGGUUCACUACGAUCCUGAAAAAGAUGUACAUAUUUACGAAGCACAGAAGAGAAACCAGAAGGAGGACUUAUAAUUGGCUAUAAUUUAUAAGAAUGUUGUCAUUGAGUGUGUCACUUAAGGUCUUAGACUGCAAAUCUAACCAUAUUUAAUGAAAUGUCUUACUGUACAAAAAGUCUAAGCCAAAGGUUCUCAGGGGAGAAAGCACAUGUGCAGUUUUAAAACAAAGCAGUGCUUUGUCCCAUUGCUGUGAUUUUUAGUCAGACUUUACUCAGUCUGAAAUGCAAUUAACAUUAAAGGAUUAAGUGUGAGAUUUCGAUUUAUGCUAUUUGUGUAUCCCAUACUCCUCCCUUUUAAUAAACAGUUUCCACUGAUGAUAUGAAGGGCCGGUAUAAAGAAGUCUUUAAAUGAGUAAGCUUUCUUGGUAAGAUUAAAUCUUACAAAUUAUUUUUAAAACCUUGUGAUAUAUACAAUGUUUAGCUGAGUUUUCUAAUUUUCUGGAUGUAAAACAAAAGGUUUAACCUAUACAUUCCUUGAGCUGUUAGUGCUAUUUAAAUCUUUUGCCCUGUUUAGGUCCUAAACACUUUUAGUUGAGUAGGAUAUGAGCUUUUUUGGGUCUCAUAUCAUGCUUUUUGCCUUAAUUUCAGGUAUAUAUAUAUAUAUAAAUAAAGGAAUUAAGUAAAAAUAAAAUUUCAGUUACUUUUUAAAAGCACCUGAAAUCUGGCCGGAUGCGGUGGCUCAUGCCUGUAAUCCCACCACUUUGGGAGGCCGAGGCGGGCAGAUCACCUGAGGUCAGGAGUUCAAGACCAGCCUGGCCAACAUGGUGAAACCCCAUCUCUACUAAAAAUACAAAAAUUAGCCGGGCGUGGUGUCAGGCGCCUGUAAUCCCAGCUACUCAGGAGGCUGAGGCAGGAGAAUCGCUUGAACCUGGGAGGCAGAGGUUGCAGUGAGCUGAGAUUGCACCAUUGUACUCCAGCCUGGGGGACAAGAGCGAGACUCCAUCUCAAAAAAAAAAAAAAAAAAAAAAAAAAAAAGCACCUGAAAUCUUGAAUAGGUUUUCUUUUUUUUUUUUUUUUUUUAAUUAAUUUAUUUUUUUUUUAUUGAUCAUUCUUGGGUGUUUCUCGCAGAGGGGGAUUUGGCAGGGUCAUAGGACAAUAGUGGAGGGAAGGUCAGCAGAUAAACAAGUGAACAAAGGUCUCUGGUUUUCCUAGGCAGAGGACCCUGCGGCCUUGGCCUUCCGCAGUGUUUGUGUCCCUGGGUACUUAAGAUUAGGGAGUGGUGAUGACUCUUAACGAGCAUGCUGCCUUCAAGCAUCUGUUUAACAAAGCACAUCUUGCACCGCCCUUAAUCCAUUUAACCCUGAGUGGACACAGCACAUGUUUCAGAGAGCACAGGGUUGGGGAUAAGGUCACAGAUCAACAGGAUCCCAAGGCAGAAGAAUUUUUCUUAGUACAGAACAAAAUGAAAAGUCUCCCAUGUCUACUUCUAUCCACACAGACCCGGCAACCAUCCGAUUUCUCAAUUUUUUCCCCACCCUUCCCGCCUUUCUAUUCCACAAAACCGCCAUUGUCAUCGUGGCCCAUCCCCAAUGAGCCGCUGGGCACACCUCCCAGACGGGGUCGUGGCCGGGCAGAGGGGCUCCUCACUUCCCAGUAGGGGCGGCCGGGCAGAAGCGCCCCUCACCUCCCGGAUGGGGCGGCUGGCCGGGCGGGGGGCUGACCCCCCCACCACCCUCCCGGACGGGGCGGCUGGCCAGGCAGAGGGGCUCCUCACUUCCCAGUAGGGACGGCCGGGCAGACGCGCCCCUCACCUCCUGGAUAGGGCGGCUGGCUGGGCGGGGGGCUGUCCCCCCCACCUCCCUCCCGGACGGGGCGGCUGGCCGGGCAGAGGGGUCCUCACUUCCCAGUAGGGGCGGCCGGGCAGAGGCGCCCCUCACCUCCCGGACGGGGCGGCCGGCCGGAAGGGGGGCUGACCCCCCCCACCUCCCUCCCGGACCGGGCGGCUGGCCGACCCCCCCCCCCCCCCCCGCCUCCCUCCCGGACGGGGCGGCUGGCCGGGCAGAGGGGCUCCUCACUUUCCAGUAGGGGCGGCCGGGCAGAGGCGCCCCUCACCUCCCGGACGGGGCGACUGGCCAGGCGGGGGGCUGACCCCCCCACCUCCCUCCCGGAUGGGGCAGCUGGCCAGGUGGGAGGAUGACCCCCCCACCUCCCUCCCGGGCGGGGCGGCUGGCCGGGCAGAGGGGCUCCUCACUUCCCAGUAGGGGCGGCCGGGCAGAGGCGCCCCUCACCUCCCGGAUGGGGCGGCUGGCCAGGCGGGGGGCUGAUCCCCCCACCUCCCUCCCGGACGGGGCGGCUGGCCAGGCAGAGGGGCUCCUCACUUCCCAGUAGGGGCGGCCGGGCAGAGGAGCCCCUCACCUCCCGGACGGGGCGGCUGGCCGGGCGGGGGGCUGACCCCCCCCACCUCCCUCCCGGACGGGGUGGCUGCUGGGCGGAGACGCUCCUCACUUCCCAGACGGGGUGGUUGCCGGACGGAGGGGCUCCUCACUUCUCAGACGGGGCGGUUGCCAGGCAGAGGGUUUCCUCACUUCUCAGACGGAGCGGCCGGGCAGAGACGCUCCCCACCUCCCAGACAGGGCUGCGGCCCAGCAGAGGCGCUCCUCACAUCCCAGACAGGGCGGCGGGGCAGAGGUGCUCCCCACAUCUCAGACGAUGGGCGGCCGGGCAGAGACGCUCCUCACUUCCUAGAUGGGAUGGCGGCGGGGAAGAGGCGCUCCUCGCUUCCCAGAUGGGAUGGCGGCCGGGCAGAGACGCUCCUCACUUUCCAGACUGGGCAGCCAGGCAGAGGGGCUCCUCACAUCCCAGACGAUGGGUGGCCAAGCAGAGACGCUCCUCACUUCCCAGACGGGGUGGCGGCCAGGCAGAGGCUGCAAUCUCGGCUCUCCGGGAGGCCAAGGCAGGCGGCUGGGAGGUGGUUGCAGCGAGCCGAGAUCACGCCACUGCACUCCAGCCUGGGCACCAUUGAGCACUGAGUGAACGAGACUCCAUCUGCAAUCCCGGCACCUCGGGAGGCCGAGGCUGGCGGAUCACUCGCGGCUAGGAGCUGGAGACCAGCCCGGCCAACACAGCGAAACCCCGUCUCCACCAAAAAAAACCGAAAACCAGUCAGGCGUGGCGGUGCGCGCCUGCAAUCGCAGGCACUCGGCAGGCUGAGGCAGGAGAAUCAGGCAGGGAGGUUGCAGUGAGCCGAGAUGGCAGCAGUACCGUCCAGCCUUGGCUCGGCAUCAGAGGGAGACCGUGGAGGGAGAGGGAGAGGGAGAGGGAGAGGGAGGGGGAGGGAGAGGGAGAGGGAGGGAAUAGGUUUUCUAUUUCAAGUCAAGAGCUGAGGUUUUCCCCUUCUGUUUUACCCUUGCUCAAAUGUCUUAAUGCAGUUCUUUCCCAAGCUUUCCCUGCUUCCUUAACAACGCAUAGGAUGACAUUAAAAGUUUUAAAUCUCAUCCCUGCCUGAGAGGUUAGCUUCCUACAUAUAAGCUCCUUUUGUAUUGGACUUGUAAUUGCUCAUUCAGUGGUAGUAUUGCCCUGUAGAGUGUAAGCUCCUUGAGGGCCAAGAAUGCUUCUGCCUCUUCCAUUGUUGCUUCCCCAGUACCUUCUGUAUAUUUCAUAACCAAAUAAUGAAAAAGAUACAUUCCAUUUAAAGGGCAUUGACUUUGGGUUAAAUGAUUGUUAUAUUGUUUUAGGAUUAUCUAUGAUACACUUUGACAUCUCACACACACACAUGAACUUUUCUUUUUACAAUGCAAAAGUUUAAACAAUAGCUUAAAUUUAGACUGCAAGAAUAUUAUAAUCUCAAUAUGGUAUUUGGUACUAGAGAUAGAUUUCUUUUAUAAAAUCUUAAAAACAGGACGUUCUCUUCCUUUUGAACCUUUAUCCCAGAGGUGAAAAUAUCCAAUAUGUUGUUUUCUGCAUAUAUUGAAGUAGUAGUUUCACUUUAAUAAAGAUGGAUUAAAAGUUG